AGUCGGAAGCAGUGUACCGGGCCGUGGAGCGGCGGCUCCUGUACCCCCGGCGCGGACCUAAAGGGGCUCGGGCCGCUCGGGCCGGGAAUGGCGGCGGCGGCCGAGCCCGGGGCCCGCGCCUGGCUGGGCGGCGGCUCCCCGCGCCCCGGCAGCCCGGCCUGCAGCCCCGUGCUGGGCUCAGGAGGCCGCGCGCGCCCGGGGCCGGGGCCGGGGCCGGGACCCGAGCGGGCGGGCGUCAGAGCCCCGGGCCCCGCUGCCGCGCCGGGACACAGCUUCCGGAAGGUGACGCUCACCAAGCCCACCUUCUGCCACCUCUGCUCCGACUUCAUCUGGGGGCUGGCCGGCUUCCUGUGCGACGUCUGCAAUUUCAUGUCUCAUGAGAAGUGCCUGAAGCACGUGAGGAUCCCGUGCACGAGUGUGGCACCCAGCCUGGUCCGGGUUCCUGUAGCCCACUGCUUCGGCCCCCGGGGGCUCCACAAGCGCAAGUUCUGUGCUGUCUGCCGCAAGGUCCUGGAGGCACCGGCGCUCCACUGCGAAGUGUGUGAGCUGCACCUCCACCCAGACUGUGUGCCCUUCGCCUGCAGUGACUGCCGCCAGUGCCACCAGGAUGGGCACCAGGAUCACGACACCCAUCACCACCACUGGCGGGAGGGGAACCUGCCCUCGGGAGCGCGCUGCGAGGUCUGCAGGAAGACGUGCGGCUCCUCUGACGUGCUGGCCGGCGUGCGCUGCGAGUGGUGCGGGGUCCAGGCGCACUCCCUCUGCUCCGCGGCGCUGGCUCCCGAGUGUGGCUUCGGGCGUCUGCGCUCCCUGGUCCUGCCUCCCGCGUGCGUGCGCCUUCUGCCCGGCGGCUUCAGCAAGACGCAGAGCUUCCGCAUCGUGGAGGCCGCGGAGCCGGGCGAGGGGGGCGACGGCGCCGACGGGAGCGCUGCCGUGGGUCCAGGCAGAGAGACACAGGCAACUCCGGAGUCCGGGAAGCAAACGCUGAAGAUCUUUGAUGGCGACGACGCGGUGAGAAGAAGCCAGUUCCGCCUCGUCACGGUGUCCCGCCUGGCCGGUGCCGAGGAGGUGCUGGAGGCCGCACUGCGGGCCCACCACAUCCCCGAGGACCCUGGCCACCUGGAGCUGUGCCGGCUGCCCCCUUCCUCUCAGGCCUGUGACGCCUGGGCUGGGGGCAAGGCUGGGAGUGCUGUGAUCUCGGAGGAGGGCAGAAGCCCCGGGUCCGGCGAGGCCACGCCAGAGGCCUGGGUCAUCCGGGCUCUGCCGCGGGCCCAGGAGGUCCUGAAGAUCUACCCUGGCUGGCUCAAGGUGGGCGUGGCCUACGUGUCCGUGCGAGUGACCCCGAAGAGCACGGCCCGCUCUGUGGUGCUGGAGGUCCUGCCGCUGCUCGGCCGCCAGGCCGAGAGUCCCGAGAGCUUCCAGCUGGUGGAGGUGGCGAUGGGCUGCAGGCACGUCCAGCGGACGAUGCUGAUGGACGAACAGCCCCUGCUGGACCGGCUACAGGACAUCCGGCAGGGAGGCCUCGAGCUGCAGAUCUCCCCGAGGUCCUCGAGGGGAACGGACAGGGGUUGUCCACAGCAAGGAAGCCUCUGUGGCCCCUUUCCUCGUUUUCCUGUUGACUUAAUUCCUGGGAGUGUUCCUGAUGCCCUGUUUUGCUGUUUUGCGGGUGAGGAGACAGAGGGCCUGGUGCGGUGGUGCCGUUCUCCCCGGCCCAGCAUCCCCGCCCCUCUCCCUGCAGAUGUCUGUGCGGCAGCCACCGUGGUGUCCGUGAGUCACAUCUACUCCUCCCAAGGCGCGGUAGUGUUGGACGUUGCCUGCUUUGCGGAGGCCGAGCGGCUGUACAUGCUGCUGAAGGACAUGGCUGUGCGGGGCCGGCUGCUCACUGCCCUGGUGCUCCCCGACCUGCUGCACGCGAAGCUGCCCCCAGACAGCUGUCCCCUCCUUGUGUUCGUGAACCCCAAGAGUGGAGGCCUCAAGGGCCGAGACCUGCUCUGCAGCUUCCGGAAGCUACUGAACCCUCAUCAGGUCUUCGACCUGACCAACGGAGGUCCUCUUCCCGGGCUCCACCUGUUCUCCCAGGUGCCCUGCUUCCGGGUGCUGGUGUGUGGUGGCGAUGGCACUGUGGGCUGGGUGCUUGGCGCCCUGGAGGAGACACGGUACCGACUGGCCUGCCCGGAGCCUUCUGUGGCCAUCCUGCCCCUGGGCACAGGGAAUGACCUUGGUCGAGUCCUCCGCUGGGGGGCGGGCUACAGCGGCGAGGACCCGUUCUCCGUACUGCUGUCUGUGGACGAGGCCGACGCCGUGCUCAUGGACCGCUGGACCAUCCUGCUGGAUGCCCACGAGGCUGGCAGUGCAGAGAACGACACGGCAGACGCAGAGCCCCCCAAGAUCGUGCAGAUGAGUAACUACUGUGGCAUUGGCAUCGACGCGGAGCUGAGCCUGGACUUCCACCAGGCACGGGAAGAGGAGCCUGGCAAGUUCACAAGCAGGCUGCACAACAAGGGUGUGUACGUGCGGGUGGGGCUGCAGAAGAUCAGUCACUCUCGGAGCCUGCACAAGCAGAUCCGGCUGCAGGUGGAGCGGCAGGAGGUGGAGCUGCCCAGUAUUGAAGGCCUCAUCUUCAUCAACAUCCCCAGCUGGGGCUCGGGGGCCGACCUGUGGGGCUCCGACAGCGACACCAGGUUUGAGAAGCCACGCAUGGACGACGGGCUGCUGGAGGUUGUGGGCGUGACGGGCGUCGUGCACAUGGGCCAGGUCCAGGGUGGGCUGCGCUCCGGAAUCCGGAUUGCCCAGGGUUCCUACUUCCGAGUCACGCUCCUCAAGGCCACCCCGGUGCAGGUGGACGGGGAGCCCUGGGUCCAGGCCCCGGGGCACAUGAUCAUCUCAGCUGCUGGCCCUAAGGUGCACAUGCUGAGGAAGGCCAAGCAGAAGCCGAGGAGGGCCGGGACCACCAGGGAUGCCCGGGCGGAUGCUGCGCCUGCCCCUGAGAGCGAUCCUAGGUAGGGGUGGCUGGGGCAGCCCAAGGGCUCGAGCCAUCUCUGCUCCCGCCAGCCUUGUUUUCAGGUGGUCUGGAGGCAGCUCCACGUCCACACAGUGGCCGGCCCUGUGGUCGGACCUGGCUACAGCCCUGACCACAGCAUCUUCCCAGUGACGGAGCGGGACCCGCCCUCAUCCCAUUGGUGACACAUGUUGGUGUCACAGCCCUCAUCCCACUGGAGACUGGUGUGCGGGUGGCAGUGUUACCCCGUGUCCCGGGUGGGCGCAGGGCUCUGGAUGGUGAGCCCUCUGCCCUGUGGGGGCCUGGUCCUCUCCUCAGGGGUGGGCACCCAUCCCUCUCCCCACUGAGCCCCUUGAGCUGGACAGUGCUGGAUGCAGGCCGUCCAGGUGGGUCUGAUCUCACUUUGUGCCCCUCGGGCCGUCCCCCUGGCCAGUCCUUAAGAGCAGCAGGCUCCCUGGUGUGUCCCUGCCCCAGCAGACACAGGCUGCCAGUCCCUCCAGCCUCACCUCCCCGCCCUGGGCAGCAGGUGUGGGCAGCGUGUGAGGCUGCCGGGUGGUGGUGACUGGUGACUUCCUUGUGUUCAGGGAAGGGAGAAGGUGCCUUCCCUUGUUUUCUGGCCUUGUUAUAUACAGAUGGCAGCUUGGAUCUCAGGUACAGCUCCAGGGGCAGGCAGUGCCCAGCUGGACCUGGUGGCCCUUUCCUAGUGCCUCUGCUUGGGGAGGAGAACCUCUGUCCACGUGGAGGCUAGGAGGUCUCAGGUGCUGCCCUGGCAGCACCAGAGUGUGGGCCGGGCCCGAGUGUCUGCCCCUCGGCCCUCAGGGUGGGGCACUUAGCACCCAGAAGGGACCAAAAGCAGGGCAUGGCGGUGCAGAGGAGUUUGGGAGGUGUAAACAGCCCAUGCACGUGGAGGAGGAGCUGGCUUUCAGCCCCAGACCCCACGCUAGCACUUUCCACGCUGCUUGCCCGCUGUUGAUGUGCAGUUCCCAGUGCCUGUGUGAGCCGACAUCUGCUCAGUCCUAUCCCUCGUCAGCGUGUGGAGACCCAGCUCCUGCAGCCCUCCUGCUCCCACGCCCCCAGACAGCUUGGUGGAGGGUCCUGCAUCUGGGCCAGGCUGGGGUGCACCCAGCCAAAGACAAAGCUGCCUCCACGUGCCCAAGGAUUCAGAUGGUGCACUGGCCCCGGGAGGAGUCUGACCAAAAAUGGAGCCCGCUCUGUGGGGAAGCCCCGACUCCCCCACGAGAAACGGUCCCACGGUGCGGAUCUCCCCCUUCCCUUGUGGGGCACAGCUGGCCUGGGCCUCCAAUCCUGCGGAGCUUUCCUGGGUGUGGCUUUGACCUCAGAAGUGGCUCUGGUUUGGCCUCAGGAGUGUGGCCUGGCCCAGCCUGCUGCAGCCUCCUGGGGGGCCCUUGAUGCCACUAAUCCCCCGACCCCCCGCAUCUGCCAAACUGCACAGACACACGCAUUGUAAGGCCGCUUGUGGCCUCCAGCGUGCACUCUUGUUUACGUCAUUGUCAUCUUCAAGACCAGUCCUUUGUGAUUAGUUUUGCUUCGCGAGCCCUGGUGUGGACUGUGGUCUGUAUGAAUCGUGUGUAACUGUGGUGAGGGGCUUGUCCUGUAUGUGAGUCUGUACCCAGGUGGGGUCUGUGCCCUGCACACCGGGCCCCUCUGUAUUUAUCGCUGCCUGAAUGCAACAGUAAUUUAUAUCCAGGACAAAUACAGUCUGGGCGUCACUAUCCUA